GGUAUGAUGACCCGGCUGCGGGGCCCCAGAUCUCGUCUCCUCCGCCGCCUCCUCACGGCAGCCCCAGCUCGCGGCUGAGAACCAGACACACCGGCGGUGAGUGGGGACGGGCAGGAGGGGUCCUCGGCGGGGAGCGACUUCCCCUCAGCUCCCUGAGGCGGGGCCGGGCCGGCCGCCGGCUCUCCUGGAGCGCCCAGCCUGCCGGGGGCGCCUUCCUCAAAGGGCCCCUGCCUGGGACCGGGCGCCGCGUCUUGCGGCCCGGCCGCUCACUGCCGCUGAGGGGAUUGCCUUCCCAGGAAGGUGGGGAGGCUCCGGGCUGGUUUUCGGGGCAACUCCCCCUGCCUCCUGCCACUUCUCGCCUGGGCGUGUUGUCCUUAAGUGACAGGGGACCGCCUUGCGUCUCCUCACUCGGCCGGUUUUUUCCCCGGCUGUCGUGGCAGGUUCCCAGUGUGUGGCUUGUGCGUGUGUACUUCACAGCUCCGCUUAUCACCAUGGUUUUGGGUUAUUUGUGCUGUUUGGGACCAGGAAGCCGUGCCUGGAGAGGACGACAGUGGGGUGGGUGUGGAAGCUUUUCUGUCGUCUCCGCUGAUGUUCUGUAGUCGUUAGGCUUGUAAUUCGUAAUGACGGUGGAGACUACGUGAGACCAGCCCACCUAAUGUAUAUCUGUACAAGGGAGAUCUAGAGGUCUGGCCCAAAGGGAAACUUUUGCUGCCACCACUUUCAAAGCUUUCGUUAAAAAAACAAAAGGGAGGGGGAAGGUGGAGAAACAACCAAAAUUCUGGUAAGGCCCACACUGUUCACAGGUCUGUGGGGAAGAGUCCCCUUUUUGUGCUUAGCAACCAAGACGUGGAGUUCCGUCUCCAGGAGCGUUGGUCUAACCUCCAGUUUGUUGUGGUGACGAGCUGUGAGCAAUGGCCUGUGUUUAUGCUGGGCGAGCUUUCUUUCCUACUUGGGGAGGGGGGUUCAGGAUGGGAGGAUGCGGGUAGGGAAGAGGGGGGGAAAACCCCCAAGCUCCAGUAAGUCUUUUCUUUACUUAAUCACUGAUUCUGUUGUAGGUAGACUCAUUUAGAGGCAGUCCUAGAUGCUCUUUCUUGUCUAUUAGUGACACUUUGGGAAUUCUCAGUAAUUGCAUCAACAUAAUACUUUCAGCUAUAGACUCUCUGUCCCAAUCUGUCCUUUAUCUUGUUUCUUAGUAACUGGUGAAAACAGCAGUGUGGCUUCCCGCUCUUGAUGAAAUAGGGUUAAAUUAAGUGGCUGAUGCCCUCAGCAAACCUACAAUUUUCCUUUUGUUUGUGUAAAGCUAUUUUUGAUCUCUGGUCUGUGGGUUUUUUUUUUUUUUUUGUAAGAUUAUAGAGAAUGCAAACUAUUACUAGCUUUUUUCAUAUGGAAGCCUAAAGCUUUCUAUAAAACAUUUUAAAAUCUAACAAAUCAUUUGACCUAAUUUUCAUUAUUCAGCUGGUGAUUUUGGAUCUUUACAUGUAAUUAUCUCAGGGUUCUGUGUUAUAAUACUGUUAUGAUGAAGGGUGGCAUUGACUUUAAGAUACUGUUCCUGGCUUGAAAGAUAUUUUAGUAAAGUACUUGCGGUUGGAACUGGAGGCAGCCAAGCCAGUAAAGUAUCUUAGAAUAAAAUGGUGAAUGAGAUCUUAUAAAUAUACUGGCUCUGGUUGGCAAGUAGAACUUUUGCUGGUGAUACCUUCAUGAAUAGUUUAUCUCUCGACACUGUAGUUUUGUGGUUUUUUGAGCAAGUUCGUUGGUAACUUGAGACUUCAAACCAAACCAGAACUUCCUUCUAAAAGAAAAAAAAAGAAGAGAUAAUCUCAAAGUUCACAAUUCUUUGGAAAAUAAACUUCUUUCAUUCUGUGCUUUUGUUUUUAUAAGCACAGCUCCAUCAAUGAUUUGUUGGUACAAAUCAGUGAGUCAUACCGGCCUUGUAAAGUUCUUACACUUGGAACUUGUGCAGCUUGUUAGUUAUAUAUUGUAACUGGUCUUGUAAUUUGAAGUAAUUUUGCAAACAUGAGCUGCUUGAUCUGCCACCUGCAUGAGUGUAUAACAGCAGUCUGUAUUUUUUAGGUCUUUUUAAAAAAAAUUUACUAUUAUUCCUCCCGUUAUCUUCCCUUCCUCUCCCUUUGUGCCAUUCUGAACACAAGUCAUCAAGAUUAUUUUCCUUUAAGUACCACUUCAACAAUCACUGGUUUGUCUUUUGGUUCCUUUUGUUUUUGUUCCUGAUCUUCCCUUUAGUUGUUGGAACCCAGCUCCUAAAUGCCUAAUAUAUUCCUGUAGUGCAUAAUUUGGCACUUGAAAAAUUUACAUCCUGUUUUCAUAUUUUUCUUUCUUUUUCAUGUGUUAUAUCAUUUCAGCAACAUUUUAAGUUUUUUGAAGUCAUUCCAAAUAAAUCUAAGUGAACUAUUGAUUUUGAUACAAAGCAACAGCCUCUGCCACACUGAAGAAGUGAGCUUUAAGCAGAGACUAGAAGGAGACGGUUUCACCAUGUUGCCCAGGCUGGAGCUCCCUGAUUUCUGGCUUGAGGCGUUGGAUGUGUGAUGGCAUCUCAUAAUUAAGAUAGAAAACUGAAGGUGGGGUGGAGGCUCGUAUGGCAUCACAGCUGCAAGUGUUUUCGCCCCCAUCAGUGUCGUCGAGUGCCUUCUGCAGUGCGAAGAAACUGAAAAUAGAGCCCUCUGGCUGGGAUGUUUCAGGACAGAGUAGCAACGACAAAUAUUAUACCCACAGCAAAACCCUCCCAGCCACACAAGGGCAAGCCAACUCCUCUCACCAGGUAGCAAAUUUCAACAUCCCUGCUUACGACCAGGGCCUCCUCCUCCCAGCUCCUGCAGUGGAGCAUAUUGUUGUAACAGCCGCUGAUAGCUCGGGCAGUGCUGCUACAUCAACCUUCCAAAGCAGCCAGACCCUGACUCACAGAAGCAACGUUUCUUUGCUUGAGCCAUAUCAAAAAUGUGGAUUGAAACGAAAAAGUGAGGAAGUUGACAGCAACGGUAGUGUGCAGAUCAUAGAAGAACAUCCCCCUCUCAUGCUGCAAAACAGGACUGUGGUGGGUGCUGCUGCCACAACCACCACUGUGACCACAAAGAGUAGCAGUUCCAGCGGAGAAGGGGAUUACCAGCUGGUCCAGCAUGAGAUCCUUUGCUCUAUGACCAAUAGCUAUGAAGUCUUGGAGUUCCUAGGCCGGGGGACAUUUGGACAGGUGGCUAAGUGCUGGAAGAGGAGCACCAAGGAAAUUGUGGCUAUUAAAAUCUUGAAGAACCACCCCUCCUAUGCCAGACAAGGACAGAUUGAAGUGAGCAUCCUUUCCCGCCUAAGCAGUGAAAAUGCUGAUGAGUAUAAUUUUGUCCGUUCAUACGAGUGCUUUCAGCAUAAGAAUCACACCUGCCUUGUUUUUGAAAUGUUGGAGCAGAACUUAUAUGAUUUUCUAAAGCAAAACAAAUUUAGCCCACUGCCACUCAAGUACAUCAGACCAAUCUUGCAGCAGGUGGCCACAGCCUUGAUGAAGCUCAAGAGUCUUGGUCUGAUCCACGCUGACCUUAAGCCUGAAAACAUCAUGCUGGUUGAUCCAGUUCGCCAGCCCUACCGAGUGAAGGUCAUUGACUUUGGUUCUGCUAGUCACGUUUCCAAAGCUGUGUGCUCAACCUACUUACAGUCACGUUACUACAGAGCUCCUGAAAUUAUUCUUGGGUUACCAUUUUGUGAAGCUAUUGAUAUGUGGUCACUGGGCUGUGUGAUAGCUGAGCUGUUCCUGGGAUGGCCUCUUUAUCCUGGUGCUUCAGAAUAUGAUCAGAUUCGUUAUAUUUCACAAACACAAGGCUUGCCAGCUGAAUAUCUUCUCAGUGCCGGAACAAAAACAACCAGGUUUUUCAACAGAGAUCCUAAUUUGGGGUACCCACUGUGGAGGCUUAAGACACCUGAAGAACAUGAACUGGAGACUGGAAUAAAAUCAAAAGAAGCUCGGAAGUACAUUUUUAAUUGCUUAGAUGACAUGGCUCAGGUGAAUAUGUCUACAGACCUGGAGGGAACAGACAUGUUGGCAGAGAAGGCAGACCGAAGAGAAUACAUUGAUCUGUUAAAGAAAAUGCUCACAAUUGAUGCAGAUAAGAGAAUUACCCCUCUAAAAACUCUUAACCAUCAGUUUGUGACAAUGACUCACCUUUUGGAUUUUCCACAUAGCAAUCAUGUUAAGUCUUGUUUUCAGAACAUGGAGAUCUGCAAGCGGAGGGUUCACAUGUAUGAUACAGUGAGUCAGAUCAAGAGUCCCUUCACUACACAUGUUGCCCCAAAUACAAGCACAAAUCUAACCAUGAGCUUCAGCAAUCAGCUCAAUACAGUGCACAAUCAGGCCAGUGUUCUAGCUUCCAGUUCUACUGCAGCAGCUGCUACUCUUUCUCUGGCUAAUUCAGAUGUCUCACUACUAAACUACCAGUCAGCUUUGUACCCAUCAUCUGCUGCACCAGUUCCUGGAGUUGCCCAGCAGGGUGUUUCCUUGCAGCCUGGAACCACCCAGAUUUGCACUCAGACAGAUCCAUUCCAACAGACAUUUAUAGUAUGUCCACCUGCGUUUCAAACUGGACUACAAGCAACAACAAAGCAUUCUGGAUUCCCUGUGAGGAUGGAUAAUGCUGUACCGAUUGUACCCCAGGCACCAGCUGCUCAGCCACUACAGAUUCAGUCAGGAGUUCUCACGCAGGGAAGCUGUACACCACUAAUGGUAGCAACUCUCCACCCUCAAGUAGCCACCAUCACACCGCAGUAUGCGGUGCCCUUUACUCUGAGCUGCGCAGCCGGCCGGCCGGCGCUGGUUGAACAGACUGCCGCUGUACUGCAGGCGUGGCCUGGAGGGACUCAGCAAAUUCUCCUGCCUUCAACUUGGCAACAGUUGCCUGGGGUAGCUCUACACAACUCUGUCCAGCCCACAGCAAUGAUUCCAGAGGCCAUGGGGAGUGGACAGCAGCUAGCUGACUGGAGGAAUGCCCACUCUCAUGGCAACCAGUACAGCACUAUCAUGCAGCAGCCAUCCUUGCUGACUAACCAUGUGACAUUGGCCACUGCUCAGCCUCUGAAUGUUGGUGUUGCCCAUGUUGUCAGACAACAACAAUCCAGUUCCCUCCCUUCGAAGAAGAAUAAGCAGUCAGCUCCAGUCUCUUCCAAGUCCUCUCUAGAUGUUCUGCCUUCCCAAGUCUAUUCUCUGGUUGGGAGCAGUCCCCUCCGCACCACAUCUUCUUAUAAUUCCUUGGUCCCUGUCCAAGAUCAGCAUCAGCCCAUCAUCAUUCCAGAUACUCCCAGCCCUCCUGUGAGUGUCAUCACUAUCCGAAGUGACACUGAUGAGGAAGAGGACAACAAAUACAAGCCCAGUAGCUCUGGACUGAAGCCAAGGUCUAAUGUCAUCAGUUAUGUCACUGUCAAUGAUUCUCCAGACUCUGACUCUUCUUUGAGCAGCCCUUAUUCCACUGAUACCCUGAGUGCUCUCCGAGGCAAUAGUGGAUCCGUUUUGGAGGGGCCUGGCAGAGUUGUGGCAGAUGGCACUGGCACCCGCACUAUCAUUGUGCCUCCACUGAAAACUCAGCUUGGUGACUGCACUGUAGCAACCCAGGCCUCAGGUCUCCUGAGCAAUAAGACUAAGCCAGUCGCUUCAGUGAGUGGGCAGUCAUCUGGAUGCUGUAUCACCCCCACAGGGUAUCGAGCUCAACGCGGGGGGACCAGUGCAGCACAACCACUCAAUCUUAGCCAGAACCAGCAGUCAUCGGCGGCUCCAACCUCACAGGAGAGAAGCAGCAACCCAGCCCCCCGCAGGCAGCAGGCGUUUGUGGCCCCUCUCUCCCAAGCCCCCUACACCUUCCAGCAUGGCAGCCCGCUACACUCGACAGGGCACCCACACCUUGCCCCGGCCCCUGCUCACCUGCCAAGCCAGGCUCAUCUGUAUACGUAUGCUGCCCCGACUUCUGCUGCUGCACUGGGCUCAACCAGCUCCAUUGCUCAUCUUUUCUCCCCACAGGGUUCCUCAAGGCAUGCUGCAGCCUAUACCACUCACCCUAGCACUUUGGUGCACCAGGUCCCUGUCAGUGUUGGGCCCAGCCUCCUCACUUCUGCCAGCGUGGCCCCUGCUCAGUACCAACACCAGUUUGCCACCCAAUCCUACAUUGGGUCUUCCCGAGGCUCAACAAUUUACACUGGAUACCCGCUGAGUCCUACCAAGAUCAGCCAGUAUUCCUACUUAUAGUUGGUGAGCAUGAGGGAGGAGGAAUCAUGGCUACCUUCUCCUGGCCCUGCGUUCUUAAUAUUGGGCUAUGGAGAGAUCCUCCUUUACCCUCUUGAAAUUUCUUAGCCAGCAACUUGUUCUGCAGGGGCCCACUGAAGCAGAAGGUUUUUCUCUGGGGGAACCUGUCUCAGUGUUGACUGCAUUGUUGUAGUCUUCCCAAAGUUUGCCCUAUUUUUAAAUUCAUUAUUUUUGUGACAGUAAUUUUGGUACUUGGAAGAGUUCAGAUGCCCAUCUUCUGCAGUUACCAAGGAAGAGAGAUUGUUCUGAAGUUACCCUCUGAAAAAUAUUUUGUCUCUCUGACUUGAUUUCUAUAAAUGCUUUUAAAAACAAGUGAAGCCCCUCUUUAUUUCAUUUUGUGUUAUUGUGAUUGCUGGUCAGGAAAAAUGCUGAUAGAAGGAGUUGAAAUCUGAUGACAAAAAAAGAAAAAUUACUUUUUGUUUGUUUAUAAACUCAGACUUGCCUAUUUUAUUUUAAAAGCGGCUUACACAAUCUCCCUUUUGUUUAUUGGACAUUUAAACUUACAGAGUUUCAGUUUUGUUUUAAUGUCAUAUUAUACUUAAUGGGCAAUUGUUAUUUUUGCAAAACUGGUUACGUAUUACUCUGUGUUACUAUUGAGAUUCUCUCAAUUGCUCCUGUGUUUGUUAUAAAGUAGUGUUUAAAAGGCAGCUCACCAUUUGCUGGUAACUUAAUGUGAGAGAAUCCAUAUCUGCGUGAAAACACCAAGUAUUCUUUUUAAAUGAAGCACCAUGAAUUCUUUUUUAAAUUAUUUUUUAAAAGUCUUUCUCUCUCUGAUUCAGCUUAAAUUUUUUUAUCGAAAAAGCCAUUAAGGUGGUUAUUAUUACAUGGUGGUGGUGGUUUUAUUAUAUGCAAAAUCUCUGUCUAUUAUGAGAUACUGGCAUUGAUGAGCUUUGCCUAAAGAUUAGUAUGAAUUUUCAGUAAUACACCUCUGUUUUGCUCAUCUCUCCCUUCUGUUUUAUGUGAUUUGUUUGGGGAGAAAGCUAAAAAAACCUGAAACCAGAUAAGAACAUUUCUUGUGUAUAGCUUUUAUACUUCAAAGUAGCUUCCUUUGUAUGCCAGCAGCAAAUUGAAUGCUCUCUUAUUAAGACUUAUAUAAUAAGUGCAUGUAGGAAUUGCAAAAAAUAUUUUAAAAAUUUAUUACUGAAUUUAAAAAUAUUUUAGAAGUUUUGUAAUGGUGGUGUUUUAAUAUUUUACAUAAUUAAAUAUGUACAUAUUGAUUAGAAAAAUAUAACAAGCAAUUUUUCCUGCUAACCCAAAAUGUUAUUUGUAAUCAAAUGUGUAGUGAUUACACUUGAAUUGUGUACUUAGUGUGUAUGUGAUCCUCCAGUGUUAUCCCGGAGAUGGAUUGAUGUCUCCAUUGUAUUUAAACCAAAAUGAACUGAUACUUGUUGGAAUGUAUGUGAACUAAUUGCAAUUAUAUUAGAGCAUAUUACUGUAGUGCUGAAUGAGCAGGGGCAUUGCCUGCAAGGAGAGGAGACCCUUGGAAUUGUUUUGCACAGGUGUGUCUGGUGAGGAGUUUUUCAGUGUGUGUCUCUUCCUUCCCUUUCUUCCUCCUUCCCUUAUUGUAGUGCCUUAUAUGAUAAUGUAGUGGUUAAUAGAGUUUACAGUGAGCUUGCCUUAGGAUGGACCAGCAAGCCCCCGUGGACCCUAAGUUGUUCACCGGGAUUUAUCAGAACAGGAUUAGUAGCUGUAUUGUGUAAUGCAUUGUUCUCAGUUUCCCUGCCAACAUUGAAAAAUAAAAACAGCAGCUUUUCUCCUUUACCACCACCUCUACCCCUUUCCAUUUUGGAUUCUCGGCUGAGUUCUCACAGAAGCAUUUUCCCCAUGUGGCUCUCUCACUGUGCGUUGCUACCUUGCUUCUGUGAGAAUUCAGGAAGCAGGUGAGAGGAGUCAAGCCAAUAUUAAAUAUGCAUUCUUUUAAAGUAUGUGCAAUCACUUUUAGAAUGAAUUUUUUUUUCCUUUUCCCAUGUGGCAGUCCUUCCUGCACAUAGUUGACAUUCCUAGUAAAAUAUUUGCUUGUUGAAAAAAACAUGUUAACAGAUGUGUUUAUACCAAAGAGCCUGUUGUAUUGCUUACCAUGUCCCCAUACUAUGAGGAGAAGUUUUGUGGUGCCGCUGGUGACAAGGAACUCACAGAAAGGUUUCUUAGCUGGUGAAGAAUAUAGAGAAGGAACCAAAGCCUGUUGAGUCAUUGAGGCUUUUGAGGUUUCUUUUUUAACAGCUUGUAUAGUCUUGGGGCCCUUCAAGCUGUGAAAUUGUCCUUGUACUCUCAGCUCCUGCAUGGAUCUGGGUCAAGUAGAAGGUACUGGGGAUGGGGACAUUCCUGCCCAUAAAGGAUUUGGGGAAAGAAGAUUAAUCCUAAAAUACAGGUGUGUUCCAUCUGAAUUGAAAAUGAUAUAUUUGAGAUAUAAUUUUAGGACUGGUUCUGUGUAGAUAGAGAUGGUGUCAAGGAGGUGCAGGAUGGAGAUGGGAGAUUUCAUGGAGCCUGGUCAGCCAGCUCUGUACCAGGUUGAACACCGAGGAGCUGUCAAAGUAUUUGGAGUUUCUUCAUUGUAAGGAGUAAGGGCUUCCAAGAUGGGGCAGGUAGUCCGUACAGCCUACCAGGAACAUGUUGUGUUUUCUUUAUUUUUUAAAAUCAUUAUAUUGAGUUGUGUUUUCAGCACUAUAUUGGUCAAGAUAGCCAAGCAGUUUGUAUAAUUUCUGUCACUAGUGUCAUACAGUUUUCUGGUCAACAUGUGUGAUCUUUGUGUCUCCUUUUUGCCAAGCACAUUCUGAUUUUCUUGUUGGAACACAGGUCUAGUUUCUAAAGGACAAAUUUUUUGUUCCUUGUCUUUUUUCUGUAAGGGACAAGAUUUGUUGUUUUUGUAAGAAAUGAGAUGCAGGAAAGAAAACCAAAUCCCAUUCCUGCACCCCAGUCCAAUAAGCAGAUACCACUUAAGAUAGGAGUCUAAACUCCACAGAAAAGGAUAAUACCAAGAGCUUGUAUUGUUACCUUAGUCACUUGCCUAGCAGUGUGUGGCUUUAAAAACUAGAGAUUUUUCAGUCUUAGUCUGCAAACUGGCAUUUCCGAUUUUCCAGCAUAAAAAUCCACCUGUGUCUGCUGAAUGUGUAUGUAUGUGCUCACUGUGGCUUUAGAUUCUGUCCCUGGGGUUAGCCCUGUUGGCCCUGACAGGAAGGGAGGAAGCCUGGUGAAUUUAGUGAGCAGCUGGCCUGGGUCACAGUGACCUGACCUCAAACCAGCUUAAGGCUUUAAGUCCUCUCUCAGAACUUGGCAUUUCCAACUUCUUCCUUUCCGGGUGAGAGAAGAAGCGGAGAAGGGUUCAGUGUAGCCACUCUGGGCUCAUAGGGACACUUGGUCACUCCAGAGUUUUUAAUAGCUCCCAGGAGGUGAUAUUAUUUUCAGUGCUCAGCUGAAAUACCAACCCCAGGAAUAAGAACUCCAUUUCAAACAGUUCUGGCCAUUCUGAGCCUGCUUUUGUGAUUGCUCAUCCAUUGUCCUCCACUAGAGGGGCUAAGCUUGACUGCCCUUAGCCAGGCAAGCACAGUAAUGUGUGUUUUGUUCAGCAUUAUUAUGCAAAAAUUCACUAGUUGAGAUGGUUUGUUUUAGGAUAGGAAAUGAAAUUGCCUCUCAGUGACAGGAGUGGCCCGAGCCUGCUUCCUAUUUUGAUUUUUUUUUUUUUUAACUGAUAGAUGGUGCAGCAUGUCUACAUGGUUGUUUGUUGCUAAACUUUAUAUAAUGUGUGGUUUCAAUUCAGCUUGAAAAAUAAUCUCACUACAUGUAGCAGUACAUUAUAUGUACAUUAUAUGUAAUGUUAGUAUUUCUGCUUUGAAUCCUUGAUAUUGCAAUGGAAUUCCUACUUUAUUAAAUGUAUUUGAUAUGCUAGUUAUUGUGUGCGAUUUAAACUUUUUUUGCUUUCUCCCUUUUUUUGGUUGUGCGCUUUCUUUUACAACAAGCCUCUAGAAACAGAUAGUUUCUGAGAAUUACUGAGCUAUGUUUGUAAUGCAGAUGUACUUAGGGAGUAUGUAAAAUAAUCAUUUUAACAAAAGAAAUAGAUAUUUAAAAUUUAAUACUAACUAUGGGAAAAGGGUCCAUUGUGUAAAACAUAGUUUAUCUUUGGAUUCAAUGUUUGUCUUUGGUUUUACAAAGUAGCUUGUAUUUUCAGUAUUUUCUACAUAAUAUGGUAAAAUGUAGAGCAAUUGCAAUGCAUCAAUAAAAUGGGUAAAUUUUCUGACUUAUGUGGCUGUUUUUGACUUCUGUUAUAGGAUAUAAAGGGGAUCAAUAAAUGACAUCUUUGAAAGUG